GGAGAUGGUCGGAAGCCAGCCCUCCCAGAGCCGGCCCACCACAGCAGGGUAGAGCCGAGAGCGGCGUCCCCUGCAGAAAGACCCCUGCGUCCCAGGCUUUGAUCGAAGCCUCCCCUCCAGGGACGUUCUUUCUGGUUGUCGUGCGGUGUCGGGGGUUCCUUACCCUCACCUCAGGUUUAGCACAGAUUCUGCGCCUGGUGCUGAAGUGACAGGGCGGCCACUCUCUUCCAGAGGCUGCUUUAGCCCCGGGGUCCCUCAUAUAUCCCUUAGGGUACCUGACGGCUCCAAACCGGUGGCCUCAACCCUUCCCACCUCUCAGGUCUUGUUCCCCAGACUCUUCUGGCCCCGCUUCAUCUGGGAGCGCGGCUGCCUGCCGCCACUUCCUCCUCUGCGCUGAGACAACGCGCAGGGGUCACCACAAGGGCCCCUGCUGCCUAUGGCCUCUAACCACACAGCACCAUGGAUAAAUGUGGACGGCCUGGGUUCAGACCCCAGCUUUGCCCUUGGCCAGAGUACCUGGCUUUGCUGUGACUGCUUCCCCGUCUACAACAUGGGGGUAAAAAUAAUCUAGGGCUUUUAUGAGGAUUUAACCUUUGUUUAUUUUUACUAAGGUGUUCAAAACAGUGCUUGGCACAUAGUAAAUUCUGUUAAUAUGUGUGUCUGCUAUUGUUUGUUUCAUAGCACAUCAUUGUGUAAAGUUGUAUCAUUUAUUUGGUAACAACUUUAUGAACUCACAGGCUUUAUACAGGGCCUAGAACAAUACUUGGUGAAGUGAGAAAAUAAGUCAAAUGGCAGGAUACAUAACGAUGGAAGACGGAGGCGCACGAGUGUCCAUCAGGACAGCUUCACCUCCUUGAGGAUUAAAGCCUAACAGUACUGAGCUAUUUGUCUGUCAAAAUGUCUGCAAAAUUGGGAAAGUCAUCAUCACUCCUAACACAAACUUCAGAGGAGUGUAAUGGGAUUCUGACAGAGAAGAUGGAAGAGGAAGAGCAGACCUGUGAUCCAGACUCUAGCCUCCACUGGAGCAGCAGCUACAGCCCAGAGACCUUCCGCCAGCAAUUCAGGCAGUUUGGCUACCAGGAUUCACCUGGGCCCCAUGAGGCUCUGAGCCGGCUCUGGGAACUUUGUCAUCUCUGGCUGAGGCCGGAAGUGCACACCAAGGAGCAGAUCCUGGAGCUGCUGGUGCUGGAGCAGUUCCUGGCCAUCCUCCCAAAAGAGCUUCAGGCCUGGGUGCAGAAGCAUCAUCCAGAGAAUGGAGAGGAAACUGUGACUAUGCUGGAGGAUGUGGAGAGAGAGCUUGAUGGACCAAAGCAGAUCUUUUUUGGACGAAGGAAGGACAUGAUUGCAGAGAAGCUAGCACCUUCAGAAAUCACUGAGGAAUUGCCAAGUAGCCAGCUCAUGCCCGUGAAGAAGCAGCUCCAGGGAGCAUCAUGGGAGCUUCAGUCCUUAAGACCACAUGAUGAAGACAUCAAAACUACAAAUGUGAAAUCUGCUUCAAGGCAAAAGACUUCUUUAGGCAUAGAACUGCAUUGCAAUGUUUCCAAUAUCCUUCAUAUGAAUGGCUCCCAGAGUUCCACAUAUAGAGGAACCUAUGAACAAGAUGGUAGGUUUGAAAAGAGACAAGGAAACCCUUCUUGGAAAAAACAACAGAAAUGUGAUGAAUGUGGCAAAAUCUUUAGUCAGAGCUCAGCCCUUAUUUUACAUCAGAGAAUCCACAGUGGAAAGAAACCUUAUGCAUGUGACGAGUGUGCAAAGGCAUUCAGCCGAAGCGCAAUUCUGAUUCAGCAUCGACGAACCCAUACUGGUGAGAAGCCCUACAAGUGUCAUGACUGUGGCAAAGCCUUUAGUCAGAGCUCAAAUCUUUUUAGACAUAGGAAAAGACACAUUAGAAAAAAAGUCCCAUAAGUAUCAUGAGGGAAUCAAAGCAUUUACUCAGAGCUAUUUCAGCACAAGGGAAGACACCAGAUGCAAACGCUCCUUAGUACAAAUCAGUGGUCUUAGUAAGCACCAGUCUCCUUUCAAGACUCAUGAAAGCCACAGGAGAGAAGGUUGAAGAUCUCAGGUCAGCAUUAUUUGCUUUUCUGCUUAUCAAUGCAGUCUCAAUUCUGACGUUUGCAAUUCCAAAGCUUAAUUCAGAUUUCCAUCCCUAUGCAGGCCUUGAAAAGGCAUUCUCAGACAUGUUCUACUAUUUUCAUUAUUAACACAUAUAAUGAAUUAGUAUAUAUCUUUUUAGACAAGUAUGUUUUUUCCCUCAUUGAGAAGGAAUGUGUGAGUUACUCAGUGUAAAAAUAGACAUUCUCCUCCAUUUCAUAACUUGAGCACUAGAAUUCUAAAGACCAAAAAUUAAAGCACUCAAAAAGAAUUCCUGGCUGGGUGCGGUUGGCUCAUGCCUGUAAUCCUAGCACUUUGGGAGGCCGAGGCAGGCAGAUUGCCUGAACUCAGGAGUUCAAGACCAGCCUGGACAACACGGCGAAACCCCGUCUCUACUAAAAUUCAAAAAAUUAGCCAGGCAUGGCAACGUGUACCUGUAAUCCCAGCUACUAGGGAGGCUGAGGCAGGAAAAUUGCUUGAACCGCUCAGACAGAGCAAGACUCCGUCUUUAAAAUAAAUAAAUAAAUAAAUAAAUAAAUAAAUAAAAAUAAAAAUAAAUUCCUAUUUUGUCUUCUGUUACUAGAUUCAAAAUAUGAACAUGCGAUUGCAGAGGCCCAAAAGAAUAUGUACUUCAAGACUAGGCUGAAGUGCCCCAGGUCACUUUCAGGAGGCAGAUAAAUAAAGGCCUUAUCUUAUGAAAGCACACAAGAGCCUCCAUACUAUUAAUAUCAAGUUAAUUUCCCGUGUUGGAAAAAAAUAAUCUCCUUUGCAAUGUAAUUUGGAAAUAAGUCAAUGGAAACAUGAAAAUGACUGCUUGUCUACAAGGAGUCAGCUAAACAUAAGGAAUGUUUUCAUAACAAUAUUAAUCUAUGGGUGCUUCUGUAAGAUGGAUGAUCAUCUUAAUAUAAAGAAAAAAGGGAGAUGAACAAAAUUGUCAAACAAGACUGAUGUACCACAAGUGUUGUCAAGUACAGUGUGUGUCGGAGAGAUGUACCACAGCUUAACUGGAAGAGGAAGCCCGUAACUGCUGAUGACAAUACUUUCAGUGUCCCCUUUUCUGGCAUAAAUCAACUAUGAAUAUGUUUCAAGCAUCACAAGACAACCUUUUCAGAGUCUUCUGUAUUCUUAGUAAGAUGAGUUUCUAGACACGCUGUCAUGAAAUGAGACCCUGGAUUUUGAUGCUCUUGUACAUAUGGACAAAUCACUGAAGUUCAAUUUAAAGGGUCCACUGCAGUCCCUUAUAAACAAUUGUUGAACCUAACCAUUAUAGUUUAUAAGUUUUAAGACAUUUAUGGGAUAUCUUAUUUGGCUUAUCUAUGGGAUAUGAGUAACUAUGUUUUACCUGCAUUUAAUUCAGCCAGAUUCCCUGUUUAAAAUUACUGAAUCGUACAUUAUUAAAAUUAUUCUGACAGUAUACAAACAACAAAAUUAUCUAUUUUCCAGAGAUUCUUGAUAAAACUCUGUAAUGUUACUACAAUAAUACAUGUAUUGUGUUUUCCAUGGUGCUACAGUUACACAAUAUGGAGGCAAACAUCAGAAAUCAAAGUCCUUGGAAUAAGGGAAGAGACUCAUAGUAAACUUCUUUGUCUGGUUGGGUUCCUCAUAAAGUAUAAAACAUUUCAUUCUCAGAAAAUCCAACCAUAUCUUAGAGUAUCUCCAGAAACUGGCUUAGAGGAGCUCCAAAUAUGUGGAAUUACCACACUCUGCUUAGUUAGUAUGCUGAUAAAUGUAAGAUUAGUAGGAGGAGAAGUGAAUGUAAAUUUUAUUAUAGAAUUUUCUGAUAGUGAUUAUGAUUUGUAGCUCUAGUGAAUAUGAAUUUUAUAUUGAGUUGUGUGUAUCUUGAGUCACUAAAAAUGUAGGAUACUUUUUAUUUGGGGCUCAUUGUCUUUGUAAUUACGGAGAGGAACAAACCAUCUAUUGAAACAACAAGUGCCUCAGAGAUGUAUAUAUUGUGAAUUACUGCUUAAUUACGGAAAGAGUUUCUUAGGUUCUAUGUGAAUAAGAUGGCAGAAUCUAAAUCAAGUAUUUUGAAGGAAGCACCCAUCUUCACUUGGUGCUGCCAUCAACUUUGUAAGAUUGCAUUCUAUUUAUUGUGAAUAAUUUGAGUGUUUCCACAGGAAAGUGGUAUGAAUCAUAUCGUCUAAGUAUAUGAUGAAUCUUUAAAGGGUGUCUCUGUGUACUUUGAAUUAUUUUGCAGUUAUGUAGGUAUCCUAAUGAGUGAAUGGUACUAGUUUAUAUAAAAGGAGAAUUCAUUGAGCUAACCUUGGUUUUAAAAAUUAGCAUUAGCACCCCCAUUAUAUUAAUUUUCAGGGAUAGUAAAUACUCCAAAAUGAAA